AUGACAACGAGUCUGCGCCCCGCGCUCAGCUGCUUCUCCGGCGGAACCCAGGCUGGACCGCGGGCCCCGGCCUGGGGGCCACUGCUGCCACCGCCGCCGCCACCUCGUCUCCUCCCCGUCCCCGCCCAGCCCCAGGUCUCCCCGCCUCACUCGGGCCCGUGGCCGGGGUCACUCCCCGCCGCCCCUCCCCGCACGGAUGCCGAAGGUGAAGGCGCUGCAGUGCGCCCUGGCGCUGGAGAUCAGCUCAGUAACUUGCCCAGGAGUCGUGCUUAAAGACAAAGAGGACAUCUAUCUUAGCAUCUGUGUGUUUGGCCAAUACAAAAAGACACAAUGUGUCCCAGCCACUUUUCCCCUGGUCUUCAAUGCCAGAAUGGUGUUUGAAAAGGUGUUCCCGGACGCAGUAGAUCCUGGAGAUGUGGUUACACAGCUUGAAUAUGAUACAGCAGUGUUCGAGUUGAUACAGCUAGUUCCACCAGUGGGUGAAACACUGUCUACGUAUGACGAAAAUACACGAGAUUUCAUGUUUCCGGGUCCAAACCAAAUGUCUGGACACCAUGAUUCAAACCGCCAGGUUACCAUGAGGAGGAUUUCUGGCCUUCGAGGAAAUGCUCCAAGGCUGGAAUUUUCUACGACUUCAGUGAUUACUGAAUGUCUGAUAAGUUCAAGGAAAUGCCACACUCAGGAUAAAUUUAUUUACCAUUUGGCUCCAGUUGAAAAAUCACAUGGCAGACUGCAAAACAGAACAUCAAGAUCACAAAAGAAAAAAUCCAAGUCACCUGAGAGAAGUAAAUACUGUAUAAAUGCAAAAAACUACGAACAGCCUACAAUUUCUUCAAAAUCACACUCUCCAUCUCCCUACACAAAAAGACGCAUGUGUGAGCUAUCUGAAGACACCAGGCGGCGGCUGGCCCAUUUAAAUCUGGGACCCUAUGAGUUCAAAAAAGAAACAGAUAAACCUCCAUUUGUGAUUAGACAUGUUGAUCCCCCAAGUCCCAGGGCUGAUACUUUAUUGGGAUCUUCUGGAAGAGACUGUGAAAGAGAUGGAUGGUCAAGGGUGCACAAUGAUCAUUCUCAUCUUGGCUGCUGCCGACCCAAGGAUUAUAAGGUUAUCAGGACACCCCAUGGGAGAGACUUCGAUGACUCUUUAGAAAAAUGUGAAGAGUAUUUGAGCCCAAGGUCGUGUAGUAAGCCCCGGCAUUCAGCGAGGACCUUGCUAGUCCAUUCAGCACCCUCAACAAUGCCAAAGCAUUCUCCAAGCCCUGUGUUAAAUAGAGCUUCUCUCAGGGAAAGAUUUCAUUCUGAUUGGUGUUCACCUUCAAACUGCGAUGAGAUCCAUGACCGGGUAAAAAAUGUCUUGAAAUCACAUCAGGCUCAUCAAAGACAUUUAUAUGAUGAGAGAGACCUAGAGAAAGAUGAUGAACUGGAACUGAAAAGAAGUCUUUUAUGUAGAGACUCUGCCUAUGACAGUGACCCCGAGUAUAGCUCAUGUCAGCAGCCACGUGGCACUUUCCAUUUGGAUGACGGUGAAUACUGGUCCAACAGGGCAGCCUCUUAUAAGGGAAAAUCCCACCGACCCAUCUUUGAGAACAGCAUGGACAAGAUGUACAGGAACUUAUACAAAAAGGCCUGUAGUUCUGCUUCACAUACACAGGAAAGCUUCUGAGACCAUCCAUGAUAAACCUCAUUAGUGUCCGUGUCAAUUUCUCAAUGAAAAUGUUUGAUGUGAUCAAUAUCUGUAUUCCUUUUUUUAAAAAAAAUGGGAUUAUAACUAAGUACAAUAGUUAUACUUGAAUAAGUUCAUUACUUCAAAUGGUAAAUUAUCAUAGGCAAGCCUUUUAAAAUAAUUAUUACAGAAGAGUCUGCUGUGUUACAAACAUUAGAGCUCUGUCACACAAUCACAACUUCCAAUAUGUGACAAGGAUAUUCUGUUACAUGUACACCUCAUAUUCCAUCUGCAAAUCCAAGAAUAGUUCCUUUCUAGAAAUGUUUUUUUUGCCUUACUCACCUUGCAAUUUUCUUCUCAUCUACUUAACUGGUUAUCUUGCCUGUGUAAGAUUUAAUUAAUAUUGACUACCUUUUCUUGGUGAUGAACAAAAUGAUAUCCUAUACAGAAAUGAAUUUCCUAAGGGUUUAAACCCUGUUUUCACUAACAUUUUCUACUUUUUCCUUUUUCAGAACAGGCUAUUCUAUUUCUUAGCUCAUAGGCUUUCUUUUUAAAGACUAUAUGAUCAUUCACUCCUUUUUCUCUGGAAGAACUGUGUAAGUUGCUUAAAAUGCAUAGCAGUUAGCUAGAAAUAUCAGUGCCAUGGAUGAUCAAAAAUUUGAAUAACUAAUUUUUAAAGAUAAAAUUCUUUGCAUGAUUUUUUUUCUAGGGCCAUACCUUUUGGUGCAACCAGAAUCAGAAAAUGGCCUCUGUUAGUAAGCUUAUAGAAACCUAAAAAUAAUAAUGGAAUUAUAUUGUAAUUUGACUGCUUGGAAUUUGUGUAAGUACCAUAUGGCCCAAGGCACUAUUAUAGUAUCCUCACUUUAAAAAAAAAAACACUUGGAACCACAAUGUGAGUAAAAUAUUAUAGCAGAACGCUUUGUGGUAGACACUGAAAAUGUUGUUGAUUGAUGGAUAGAAUUAACUUCUCCUCCCCCACCCCAGCACACACCUGUGAAGCCAAUGAUACUAUAAAGACAUAAAGAAAUCAGCUACUUUAUAUUUAAUAGAGAGUGAGGGGAGGGAAAGGAGAGUGUAGGAAUAAGUGAACUGGGCUUAUAGUCUUGAAGAGUUGCCUAAAAGAUAAUAUUUUCUCAUUGACUCUGUUUUUGAUUAAUUUUACAGUUAUGAUUGAAAAAGAACAAAAUGAACUUCCUUUAAAAUGAAAUUAAAAUGUGAAACUUGCUGACUUAUUUUUGUAGUAGAACUUGUUAACAUCAUGUUAAGGGUGCUUUAGUAUCACAGUCUGUGAUAUAUCAGAAAGGGCAUUAGAGCUAUCUCUAUGAGCCAGGAGUCCUAGGCUUUAGUAUCCCAUGUCUGCCGUUUUCUAGCUGAGUCUAUUUAAUUCUCAGAUCCUUUGUUUCCUCAGCUAUCAAAUGAUAAGAAUGUAGUAGACCCCAAACUAUGUUCUGUGGACCAAGAUCACUGUUUUAGGAGAUAAUCGUAGGAAUGUAGGUAUAAGUAUGUAAUUGGCCAUCUAAGUUUAGGAAAAUCUGUUUGCUACACACAUACACACACACACACACACACACACACACACACACACACCUCUUAGAGAGUCAUAUGUAGGAUUAUAGAGGUAAAAAGAGAUGAUAUUAAUGCUGGAAUAGCGCCUGUAAACUGGGGCUGUCUACAGCAAAUUAGGAUAUAUGGUCACUGUGCUCAUUGUGAACAGUAGCUUGUUCGAGGCUUUAAGAAAAUUCUGGUAUAAAUCUGUCUUACUCUGCAUCUAGUAGACAGCCUGGCAUGUAAUUGAUGUUCCUUAAAUAUUUAUCGAAUUAACCCAGAAUUUUCUAAACUAAAUUUAGCAUGUACCACUAUUUGUUAUUCUUGCCACCACCCCCCAUUCCCCUAGCUCCUCACACUACCUGCCAAUGUCAUCCUAAGGUACAUGUGGAUACCUAGGUUGUAGAAAUGCUGGACUACACAAUUGCUGAGUUACUCUCUGGCUGUAGAUUAUAUGAUGAGGUAUUUUACAAUCAGCUUUUGAAGGUCAACAUUGAAUAAUGCUCUUUUAAAAAAAUUAUAUCCUCAGUGUUUUUCCAUGGAAAAAUAAGUGAAAAUUCUUUUAAGAGUUGCUGUUUGGUGAAAAGAACAAACAUGACUUUCAAAGAAAAUGUUUUACUAUCACCAAAAUCUCCCAAGUGAAUAAGUACCACAGAAAUUACUUAUUGCACCUGUAUCUGCCAUUGGCUGUGAAAAAGGCUGCAAAAAGUAGGGCUGAAAGGGAAACUUUAGAAACUAAUACUCUGAAAGAUGUUUUCCUAUGGAUUAAAUUUAGUGUCUUUCUGAAAGUUGGGGGCAAAUUCCCAGAUACUAAUAGCAUCUUUGCUAAGUGUCUGAUUAUCUUCUAUCCCCUAGGAGGAAAGAGUGGUCCAUGUUGCUGUAACUACUACUAUGAGUGCUUAUGCUGUAUUGUUUUUAAAGAGUAAAACCUUUAAGUACUAAUAGUUGUCUUUUCUCAUUCACAGGAGCAGAAAGGUGCAGUUGUUUAUUCUCUUAGCCUUUUUUUUUUCCUGUAUUUCCCACAAAUCUAGAAAUAAUUAUUGGAGUUAAUAUGAAAGAUAAAUAGGCUUUUCUUUUUACUUUUUAAUUUUUUUCUUUAAAUCAUAAAAAACCUUGGGAUUUAGAAAAAUGUCAAAAUCGACAAAUAAAGAUGAAUCAUUGGAAUGAGACUCUUCCUUGGUUCUACUAGCUAGUUAUAUAACCUUAUUUAAGUCAUUUAUGCUUCUUGGAGCUCAGUUUUCUCACCAACAAGGUGAUAAAAGGGUUAAUUUAGAAUGAUCCUUUGACAUUUCAUAAUUGUACAAUUAAUAUGUACGAUCAGGAAGUCCUAGGCAGGCAGAGUUGUUUUCUGAUUUCCAAAGAUUAAGCCCCUGAUGAAAAAUCUGGAACAAAUAGAGAAUUUUCAUUAUUGUGUUCAUUUGCUAAUAAUAGCUUUAUUGAGAUAUAAUUCACUCUGAAAAAGUAUACAAUUAAGUGGUUUUUACUAUAUUCACAGAGUUGUGCAACAAUAACCACUCACUAAUUACAGAAUAUUUUAUAACUCCCAAAAGAAAUCCUGUAACCAUUAGUGAUCACUUCCCACUACCUCCUCCCCACAACUCCUGGAAACCACUAUAUGCUUUUUGUCUCCAUGCCUAUUCUGGACAUUUCAUAUAAAUGGAACCAUACAACAUGUGACCUAUUGUAUGUGGCUUCUUUCACUUAGCAAAAUAUUUUGAGAGUUCAUGCAUGUUGUAACACGUAUGAAUACUUCAUUCCUUUUUAUUACUAAAUAAUAAUCCAUCAUAUGAAUAUA